GUAGGGACCCGGCGCCGAUGAAACCGACCAAACUGGAGUUAGCUACCGGACUGUCCCGCGAGCGAAAGUUGGAAAUAAUACCUAAACCUACUUCUUGACAUGGUGUCAAAACAGAGCUUUUGCUGAGAGUUUGAUUUAUAAAGAAAUUAUGGUUCGACUGACCUUGGAUCUAAUUGCCAGAAACAGCAAUCUUAAACCCCGAAAAGAAGAAACCAUUUCACAGUGCCUGAAGAAAAUAACUCAUAUAAAUUUUUCAGACAAAAAUAUAGAUGCAAUUGAAGACCUCUCUCUUUGCAAAAAUCUUAGUGUUUUAUAUUUAUAUGAUAAUUGUAUUAGUCAAAUCACUAACCUGAAUUAUGCCACAAAUCUGACCCACUUGUACCUACAAAACAAUUGUAUUUCAUGUAUAGAGAACCUCAGGUCAUUAAAGAAACUGGAAAAACUGUAUCUGGGAGGCAAUUACAUUGCUGUCAUAGAAGGUUUAGAAGGAUUAGGAGAACUAAGAGAGCUUCAUGUUGAGAAUCAGAGGCUUCCCCUUGGGGAAAAGCUUCUGUUUGAUCCAAGAACUCUUCAUUCUCUGGCAAAAUCCCUCUGUAUAUUGAAUAUCAGCAAUAAUAAUAUUGAUGACAUUACAGACUUAGAACUACUAGAGAAUCUUAAUCAGCUCAUAGCCGUUGACAACCAACUUCUGCAUGUGAAGGAUUUGGAGUUUUUACUGAACAAGUUGAUGAAGCUGUGGAAAAUUGAUCUAAAUGGAAAUCCUGUUUGUCUCAAACCAAAAUACAGGGACAGACUGAUAUUGGUGUCCAAAUCACUGGGUACAUAUUUAUAUUAAUAUAAUUUUUAAGAGAAUGACACCUAGUUAACUUUUUGGUUAUUUUACCAGCAAGCUUUCAGAAAUAUAAAUCUGACAUCUGGAUCUGUGAAAAUUGUCAACUUUAAAUUCAAUAUUUUGAAUAAGAGCAAAAGUUAAAAUUGACAAAUAAAGCAUGAAAAACAUCUGCUGUUCAGAAGUAAUUAAAGCACCUGAUACUUAUUCCUUAAGGAGGAUAUUUUGCUAUUACCAAUAAAAAUGGUUAGUCAUAAAUGUGUAGAACUUGCUGACCUUUUGCCAAACUUUCGUUAGCACAAAUCCUUUGAUGAUCCCAAGAGACUCCUUAGCUCUUGGUUCUGUAGAUAAAAUUGAUCAAAGUUUUCAUUGCUUGACAUUUGCCAAAUGUUACCCUAAGAACAUACAGGAAUCCCUUUCGUUUGAUAGGAGAGCUGGGUGACGAGACCCUUUAUGAGAUCCUUACAAAUAACAUUCCUGAAUGUGCACCAUACUGGGGGAAAUGGACAAAAACACUCGAUUAAUAGUGACCAAGUGACACAGCAUCAGAAAGAUGGGCAGUGACCUCUCACGAAGGCUAUGGGAGUCAUUUUAUGUUUUUUAGGUUACCCAGUCCUCACCAAAUAGAGUGACAAUCCACAUAUUUGGUUUACUUAGCAUGAGUGGAAGCAAAUUUUGUAUUGAGAGAAACUUAUUAAAAUGAAAUAAAUCUCAUAGUUCUAUAAUCUUGAA